CCUCCCUCAUCUUCUUUGUCAUCUGGCACGUAAGGCCGGGCUGGGGCUGGGGCUGGGGGCGGGGUGGGGGGCAGGGGCCACGCGGAGCUGGAGGGACCCAGGGCGGGUGGUCUCAGAGCCCAGGGGAAACUUGCUAUCCCCCAGCCGUCGGCUUGUCGGCUUCGCCCCCAUUAACACCCCCCGUGGUCGGCUUUCUUCCCGGGGCCCCCCUUCCUCCGCCGCCCCCGCCUGUCUGUGUGUAUGUCAGUCGGUCUCUGACCCCCUCCUCUGCCCUCGUCCUCUGCUCCCAUGCAGCCCGUGAGGUGGGGGGUGGAAUUCUGGCAUUUUUGUUGCUUUAUCUUCUAUGUCCCCCCCCACCACCAUCCAGCCGCCUCCAUUAGUCCGUCGGGCAGUUUGUCUGUCUGCUGCCCCCCCCCCCCCGCCUUUGUGGGUUUUUCCAGCCAGAGUGAUGGAGCUGGUUGCUAUGGCAACUGCAUCUGUUUACAGGACCCACAGAUCUCAGAGUCCAUUAACCCUUUGCCUUCCCAGCCCCCUCCCUGACCAAGCAGCAGUUGGCUCUCAUCAGCCCCCAGAGACCUAGCCCCCACCACCGGCUCACCUUGGGUUUCCCUACCCCUCCUGUUGGGGGCUUCCCAGCCCCCCAGGUUUCCUCUCCAUUUUCCAGCUUCCCUCCUCUUCCUGUCCCCCUUCCCCUUUGUCUCUCACAUACCCCUUGGUCUGUCCCUCGCCCUGGCCUAGCCUCACACCUGGUUCUUCAAAAUGUCCAUUCCUCAUCCUGCAUCCGACCCAUCGCUUCCCCCAGGCUCCCUCCUCCUCCCCUCCCGCUCCUCUCCUCCAGGGCCUCCUCUGCCUGGCUCCCGUCCCCUCACUACAGAACUAUCAAUCAGCCUCCAGCUGGUUGUUGGGGGCCCCUGGCCCCACUUUACUGCCCUCCGUCCCCACCCCCACCCAAACCCCGUGCCUGUUUCUGUAACAGCCUGCCCAGCUCGGCCCUGGCUGGCUCAGCUCAGCAUCCUCUGCUCACACCUCCCGCGCACACCUCCCUGAUUGUCAUUCCCUUUCAGGGGUCCUCUUAUCCCUCCCUCAAUCCCAUUUCCCAUAGCCCUUCCCUCCUUCCUCCCGGUGCCUCACCUGCUUCUUUCCCGGGCUCUCCACUUCCUCUCUCCUUUCUCUUCCUGGGACCUGCCGCCUGCUCCAUGGUUCCCCCUGCGCUCCCUUUGCCAUCCCCUGCCACCUUGCUCUUUGACAUCGGGAAUCCAUAGACUGAACCCCUACUGUGUGAAGAGUGAGCCCCCAAAGGCACCUCAGCACACACCCCAGCUCCAGCCCUGUCACUCCUUGGCCUGGCUCUGCUCUCUCUCUGGGUCUUGGUUGCUUUGUCUUUCCCCCUCUCCCCCGCACCCCGAGUUACUCUAUUUUUCUUUCUGUGGGGUAGGGGCAGGAGGGCUAGGGUUCUAAGGACUGGAGGGAGCUGGGGGCCACAGGCUAGGGAAUGCAGAGCUGACCAGCUCCUGGGAGAAGGGCUCCUGGAAUUCAAGAAGCCUCUUUUUGGGGCCUUCCCCACCCAGGGCCUUCCCACAGCCCCUGUGGGGUCCCUGUCCUCAGGGGAUCCUCAGCAGUUUAUCCACCACGCCUGCAUUGAUGCUUCCCAAAGAUCAGGCUCUGGGUGGCUUUGAGGGGGUCAAGGAUGAAUAAAACCCAGACUUUGCCCUUGUGGAGUGCCCAGGCUGGGAGGAAAGGCCCAAGCUUUGAAGAAAUGUCUUUGUUCAUUCAACAGAUAUUGAUUGAGCACCUGUGUGAGGUACUCUGUCCACUCAGCCAUUUAGCUGGACAAUCUUAGCAAGUCAUUUGUCCCAAGUCUGGUUCCUCGCCGGCAAAGUGGACCUGUGCACAUCAGAGUGCCUAGUGCGGCCUGCUGGGUGGUAGGGGAUAGGAGGCGUGGUCCUCAGUCCACAGCUGCUAAGAACUAGACUCUUAACAGGGCGGGACCCCAGAUCCCACUCCAGACCCUCAGCCCAGGCCCCAGUGGUUCCUAGGCAACCCUGGCGGUGAGUGACGCGUGUCAGCUGUCACCAUGGGGGAUUGUUUGUUCCGGGGGGCUGAGUCAGCGCCAGGCAGCCUGGGGGGUGGGAGGGGUGACGCCCGCCGCCUGCUGGUGGUGCCAGCUCUGGGGUACAGACGGCACCCUUCUGCUCCCUGUGGACCCUGUUGCUGUGCGUGCCAAGUGGCGCUGCCCAGAGUCAAUGGGGAGCUGGGCGGGGAGGGGGGAUGAUCCAGAUGGCCUCAGCUCCCUCCAGGAAGCCCAUGUUCUUUCUCUCUGAGCCGUCUGGGGCCUGGGAUGCCUGGGGGUGGUGGGCCUGCUGCCUCAUCCUAGGGCUGGAGCCGACAGGAGGGGACCCCAGCAGGCUCCUCUGCCAGCCCAUUUCCCCCAAGUCACCUGUCAGCUCCUUCCCAUCCCAUCAUCCCCUCAAACACUUGCUCCCCUGGAGAGUUUCCACCCGUGAGGACACUGCCGUCUGCCAGACACCCCAACACCUGAAGCCACCUUAGAUUUCUGCCUUCACUUCUCAGCCAUUUGAACCCUCUGGAGUCUGGCUCCUAAAGAGCUGUAGAAUCCCAUGCACGCCUUCCGUCUCCACUACAACUCUCCUCACUCAGACCACCAUCAGCCCUGCCCCUAACCCUCCAAACCGUCCCCUUGCUGGUCUGGCCUGAGUAUGACACAGUGGUUAGGAAUUUUAACUCUGGAGUCACACUGGGUUAGAAUCCACUAACCAGCCGUGUGGCCCUGGACAAGUCACUUAACCUGCCUCAGCUUCCUCAUCUGCAAAACAGACAUGAAAAUAAAACUAGUACCUAAGUCAUAAGGUUGUUAAGAAUUAAAUGAGUGAAUCCACAUACCGGCCAGGAGAAGCACCACUUAGAUCUCAGCUGUGACUGUCAGUGAGCUCGGAUUUCCUGCCCCACCAAUCCUGAGACAUGGACCAAUCCUAAGACAUGGACCUGACCACCCCACUCUGCUGCUGUGUACUCUUCAAUGCCUCCCCCCAAAAUUUUUGUGUUAAAAUCAUAGCCUUUGAUGAGCUGCGGACCGACUUCAAGAACCCCAUCGACCAGGGGAACCCUGCGCGGGCACGCGAGCGUUUAAAAAACAUCGAACGCAUCUGCUGCCUCCUGAGGAAGCUGGUGGUCCCAGAAUACUCCAUCCACGGCCUCUUCUGUCUGAUGUUUCUGUGUGCAGCAGAGUGGGUGACCCUGGGCCUCAACAUCCCCCUCCUCUUCUACCACCUCUGGAGGUACUUCCACCGUCCUGCAGAUGGCUCUGAGGUCAUGUAUGAUGCGGUCUCCAUCAUGAAUGCUGACAUUCUCAACUACUGCCAGAAGGAGUCCUGGUGCAAACUUGCCUUCUACCUGCUCUCCUUCUUCUAUUACCUGUACAGUAUGGUUUAUACGUUGGUGAGUUUCUAAGGGGGAAGCCGGCCAGGGAGCGAGCCCAGAACGGACCGGACGCCUGUGCACCCCCAGCCCUGCCCCUUGGCCGCAGAGGCCUCAGCCCUGGGGAGGGAGGGGGCACUGGUGCCCCCAGCCUCUCCAACCCCCAAACUGCUGCUGCGGGGAACCCCCCCCACCCCGCCUUCAGAGCCCUCCCCCUUGGACUAGAGCGGCUGGGCAGAGCUCUAAACAGGGGCAGGGGCUCCUCUGCCAGCCUGUGGGCAUGGCAGUCAUUCCUGGAAGGGGCAGGACCUCCGGCCUUGUCCAUUUCGGGGGAAACUUGGGCCCUGCCAAGGGGCAGAGCUUGACCCUGGAAAUUCUGGGCCAUCCCCCUCCACCCCCACCCUGAGGCUCCCCCUGCAGGUGGGGGGGUACCCGCACCGGGAAUGAGCAGGCUCAGCAGGGGGGCAGCCCCACCCCUAGUCUGCCCUCCCCUCUCCCCCAGGCUCUUUCUCCAGCCCUGUCUCCAUCUGCCCCAACCUCAGCCCACCUUGUCUCUUGGACCUAUUUUCUAUGUCGCCUGGAGGAGUCCGGCACCCCCUCCCCGGCCAUUUGUGACAAAAUAUGAAUAAACUACUGCAAAUA